GUCAUUUCCUGGGCCAAGUUGGGACCCGGACGGCCUCACCAUGAUGAAACGGGCAGCUGCUGCUGCAGUGGGAGGAGCCCUGGCAGUGGGGGCUGUGCCCGUGGUGCUCAGUGCCAUGGGCUUCACUGGGGCAGGAAUCGCCGCGUCCUCCAUAGCAGCCAAGAUGAUGUCCGCAGCAGCCAUUGCCAACGGGGGUGGUGUUUCUGCGGGGAGCCUGGUGGCUACUCUGCAGUCCGUGGGGGCAGCUGGACUCUCCACAUCAUCCAACAUCCUCCUGGCCUCUGUUGGGUCAGUGUUGGGGGCCUGCUUGGGGAAUUCACCUUCUUCUUCUCUCCCAGCUGAACCCGAGGCUAAAGAAGAUGAGGCAAGAGAAAAUGUACCCCAAGGUGAACCUCCAAAACCCCCACUCAAGUCAGAGAAACAUGAGGAAUAAAGGUCACAUGCAGAUGCA